AUGCACUCCAUCUCUGGCUCUGAGGGCGCUCCCUCCUCUCAGCCGGGCAGCCUGGCCUCUCCUGCCCAGACCUGCGGUCCCAGCAUCCCCCAGAGCCAGGGAACAGGCCCAGCGGGAGGGGGUUUUAUGUUUUGUUUCAAACAGAAAACACAACCUUAUUUUUCUUUACAAAAGCAAAAAAGGAAACCAAAAAAGAUACAGCCUUUGAAUGAUGCCUGCUGGCUGUCUGUAUUCGUUUGCUUGGGCAGCUCGGGCCUUCCAGGUAGGGCAGGGUCCCUGCUAAGGGGGCUCUCAUCCACUUUCUCUUUCCUCUUCAACGGGGGGUUCUGGAGUGGGGGGCUCGGGUUGGGGUGGCCACAGUGUGACCAGACAGUGUCCCUGGAGGGGCUUAGGGAUUUGGACAGGAGACUCGCUGCCUGGCUGAGCCUGGGCCGGAAGGACACCCCAGAGUUUGCUGCGCAGAGAAGGGUGUCCAGGCAGGAAAUGCUCAGCUCAGCUCUUCAGAAAAGCCUGAGCCCACCAGCCAUCCCUGACCGUCCUUGCCCCUGGCUGCAGGGACCACGGUCAGGUUGUGAAAAAGACCUCGUCUUCCUCAGAGAGGGCUUAGAGCUGCUGCACGGCUCCAUGCUGAGGCGGCGGGGAUGGGGAAUGGCCAGGGUGUCACAGCACAAGCUCUGGGGUCACCUUUCUGGUGACUGGGAUCUGCAUUUCUGUUGGCUUCAGUUUGACACGGGAGUAACAGGACGGCCAUCCGGGGCUGAUAUGGGGACCCUUAAGCCACAGCACAACGCAGAGGGAGCUCUACCAAGACUUUGUAUUUCUGAAGACCAGGUGCUCCACCCAGCCAGAGACUCAGGACUCAGCUGGUCCUGUGGCCCCUACCCAGAAGUGGAAUCAGUAGAGAGGACCAGUUUCCAUACCCCUAUGAUUGCAUCCCCAACCAGUCAGCCACACCCACCCUCUAGCCACCUGCCCACCAAACUAUCUUUAAAAACCCUAGUCUCUGAAUUUUCCAGGAGGGUAAAUUGAGUAACAGCAAAACUGUGGUCUCCUGUUUAACCAACUUUGUGUGAAUUAAACUCUUUCCUUUGCAAUUUCCA